GCACUCCAGACGCCAAGGAGGUCGAGGACAGGAGGUGCUGUCGGUGUGCCUGAGGCAGGGGGUCCGCCCUGCGCCCCACCCAGCCCCAACGCCAGCCCGGACGCCGGUGGGAACCGUGUGCCUCCUGGAUCCAGGGGACCUCUGAGUGACCGCAGGGCCGGGGUCCCCUGUCACCCCACGGCCAGGGCAGGGAGCGCUGGACACCGGGUCCCACCGGCCCUGCCAGUUCCUCUUCCGGGCUCGCGGGCUCCCAUGGCCCUCGGGCCCAGCGUGGUGACCCCGGGGGAUGGAGCCGUUCCUCAGGAGGCGGCUGGCCUUCCUGUCCUUCUUCUGGGACAAGAUCUGGCCGGCGGGCGGCGAGCCGGACCAUGGCACCCCCGGGUCCCUGGACCCCAACACUGACCCAGUGCCCACGCUCCCCGCCGAGCCUUGCAGCCCCUUCCCUCAGCUCUUCCUUGCGCUCUAUGACUUCACGGCGCGGUGUGGCGGGGAGCUGAGUGUCCGCCGCGGGGACAGGCUCUGUGCCCUCGAAGAGGGGGGCGGCUACAUCUUCGCACGCAGGCUUUCGGGCCAGCCCAGCGCCGGGCUCGUGCCCAUCACCCACGUGGCCAAGGCUUCUCCUGAGACGCUCUCAGACCAACCCUGGUACUUUAGCGGGGUCAGUCGGACCCAGGCACAGCAGCUGCUCCUCUCCCCACCCAACGAACCAGGGGCCUUCCUCAUCCGGCCCAGCGAGAGCAGCCUCGGGGGCUACUCACUGUCAGUCCGGGCCCAGGCCAAGGUCUGCCACUACCGGGUCUCCAUGGCAGCUGAUGGCAGCCUCUACCUGCAGAAGGGACGGCUCUUUCCCGGCCUGGAGGAGCUGCUCACCUACUACAAGGCCAACUGGAAGCUGAUCCAGAACCCCCUGCUGCAGCCCUGCAUGCCCCAGAAGGCCCCGAGGCAGGACGUGUGGGAGCGGCCACACUCCGAAUUCGCCCUUGGGAGGAAGCUGGGUGAAGGCUACUUUGGGGAGGUGUGGGAAGGCCUGUGGCUGGGCUCCCUGCCCGUGGCGAUCAAGGUCAUCAAGUCAGCCAACAUGAAGCUCACUGACCUCGCCAAGGAGAUCCAGACACUGAAGGGCCUGCGGCACGAGCGGCUCAUCCGGCUGCACGCAGUGUGCUCGGGCGGGGAGCCUGUGUACAUCGUCACGGAACUCAUGCGCAAGGGGAACCUGCAGGCCUUCCUGGGCACCCCCGAGGGCCGGGCCCUGCGUCUGCCGCCACUCCUGGGCUUUGCCUGCCAGGUGGCUGAGGGCAUGAGCUACCUGGAGGAGCAGCGCGUUGUGCACCGGGACUUGGCCGCCCGGAACGUGCUCGUGGACGACGGCCUGGCCUGCAAGGUGGCUGACUUCGGCCUGGCCCGGCUGCUCAAGGACGACAUCUACUCCCCGAGCAGCAGCUCCAAGAUCCCGGUCAAGUGGACAGCGCCUGAGGCGGCCAAUUAUCGUGUCUUCUCCCAGAAGUCAGACGUCUGGUCCUUCGGCGUCCUGCUGCACGAGGUUUUCACCUAUGGCCAGUGUCCCUAUGAAGGGAUGACCAACCACGAGACGCUGCAGCAGAUCAUGCGAGGGUACCGGCUGCCGCGCCCGGCUGCCUGCCCGGCGGAGGUCUACGUGCUCAUGCUGGAGUGCUGGAGGAGCAGCCCCGAGGAACGGCCCUCCUUCGCCACGCUGCGGGAGAAGCUGCACGCCAUCCACAGAUGCCACCCCUGAGUCCUCACGUGACCCAACGCUCUGGGCUCCAGCCAGGCCAGCCCCUCCUCCCUGCAGAGCGCCAACUCGAAGGGAUGCCGGUCUGCCGGACCGAGGAGCCUCUGGCUGUGGGCCUCAGGCCCUGGCGUGCACACAUGUUCGUGCACCAGGCAGACGUGCAGACGGAGGGCUGGGGCUGACGUCCCCCGUGCAGUGUGACUCGUGCAGACGGAGGGCUGGGGCUGACGUCCCCCAUGCAGUGUGACUCGUGCAGACGAAGGGCUGGGGCUGACGUUCCCCGUGCAGUGUGACUCGUGCAGACGGAGGGCUGGGGCUGACGUUCCCCGUGCAGUGUGACACGUGUCCCUGGCCUCUCAAGAGAGACAACGGCACAGGAGGGUGGGUAGAAGCCUCGGAGGCUCUGGGUGAGGAACCCUGAGCCCUGUGUGUCUCCUGCCUGGGUCCCCUGGACUCCCUCCCAGGGUGAAGAGCCAAAGGCCCAGUUCUCUCCCUAGUCCCAGCUUGGGUUUGUGGAAAUGACCAGUGCUGACUCCCAGGCAGACCGUGGUGUUGACCCCACUGGAUGUGUGGUAUGUAGGCACGGGGUGGCACCGUCACCUGCCCCUCACAGACACACUGGCGGCCUGUGCACAAACCCACUCACGCACACAGCACUCAGUAAGCCGGGACUGACCCACUCAGACACGCACACAGGCGCACAUCACACACAGGCUCAGCCCCCCAAACCCAGACCCAGGAGCUGGAGCGUACGGGUCCACGUGGCUAGAAAAUGCAGGUUGGAGCGGCCCCCAUGCCGCCCGGACCCCCAGCCCAGGACAUCAUGGUGCCCAGAGAGCGUGAGCCCCAAGGGCAUUGGCAGGAGCUGCCGAUUCCAUCUCCCUGGGUGGGUUCCAGGUGGCACAGGAAGGGUGGGCCGGGAGGCUUGGUGACCUGGGAGCUGCCCUUGGAGGCUAUUUCCAGGGGCCUCAGGGUGGGCCGUGGGGGAUUUGGAGUCUUCUGCCUGUGCAGGGUCAGGCAGGGUCGGUUGGGGGCUCGGAGGUAGAUGCCAUGGUAUGCUGGGCAGCAAGUGGCUCAGGAAGCCUCUGGGUGUGAGUCCUCGGGGGUCACCAAGGCAGGAGGGGGCAGGGAUGUGCAGGGUCCGCCCUCGUCUCCCCACGUCUGGCUCAGGGAAGCUUCUGCUCAGGUCUUCGUGAAACACGUCAAGAAGCAAGGGGGCCGGUGGGGUCUGUUUGUGGCCCCCGGAGACCCUGCCCCCCACCCUCCUGGGAGCCCAGGUUGGCAGCUGUGCCCAGAAGGCUUUCGGGGACAGAAAGUUUGGAGACAAGUUCAGGCCUGACUGAGUCCUUGUCCCCUAGAGUUGGGGUCAGCUCUGUACCUGCUGAGCCGAAGUGCUGAUGGCUGCCGUCCACAGGCCCCGGCCAAAGCCUGGCUCAGGAGGGAGCUAAGAGAUGAGACUCCCGUGUGCAGAGACAGGUGGCCCCGGGGAAGGAAGAGGCCACUCGGAGGCUCCGAGAACGGAGGCAGCGCGGGGGCUUCCUGGGGCCCGUGCAUCGGAGGAACAAGGCCAAGCGGAGGGAAGCAGCAGGAACCAGGACCCCUGCAGAUGGUGGAGGCAAGAGGCUUUAUCUGAGCCUUUGGGACCCUGGCCACCUGCCCAGCUCCAUCUGCAUGGGAGAACCUAGGGGAGGGGCUGGUUCUGGUACCUGGGCCCACUGAGGCCUUGAGCUGAGCUUCCAGUUCUGGCAGGUCCCCAGCACAGCAGCCUGGGGGCUCCUCUGGCACAGAAGGCCUCGCCCUCUGUGCUCUCUGCAGCCGCCACUGGGAUUAAGGGGACCAGGUGUGUCUGUGGCACCUGUGCCCUCCUAGGCAUCUCGCCAGCCACCAGCUGAACAGGUUUGGUGCUCCUGGGUAUCUGGGAGGGGCUGGGGACGUUCCUGCCUCCUGGUGUGGCUUAGACUGAAAGUCCUGCACGUCCGAACUCAGGGAUACUCGAGGCUUCCUGGACAUAGACUCACGGGCCCAGAGUCUGGCCGGGCUCUGAGGGACGCUGCCCGGCCAGGUGCCCCGGCACCCUCCUUCCGCAUUCCCCACCCCCCACCCCUCCCCCUGCAUCCUCCCCAACCGACCCCAGACAGAGCUGGGAGGGCCUGAGGGACACUGCCCAGGCCGGCACCCCGCUGCCCCUCCCCACCUUGGUCAGCGCUGAGCUGGGCUGCCCAGAAAUCUAUGAGCCUGUUAAAUAAUCCAGAUUAUUGUUCUUAAUCUCAAAACAAUGAGUGGAAGGUGCCAUUAUUUCUCUUUGCAAUAAAAAUAAAAGUUGAAAUACGCA